GCACUUCCGGGUGUUGUCUGGCCGCCGUAGCGCGUCUUGGGUCUCCCGGCUGCCGCUGCUGCCGCCGCCGCCUCGGGUCGUGGAGCCAGGAGCGACGUCACCGCCAUGGCAGGCAUCAAAGCUUUGAUUAGUUUGUCCUUUGGAGGAGCAAUCGGACUGAUGUUUUUGAUGCUUGGAUGUGCCCUUCCAAUAUACAACAAAUACUGGCCCCUCUUUGUUCUAUUUUUUUACAUCCUUUCACCUAUUCCAUACUGCAUAGCAAGAAGAUUAGUGGAUGAUACAGAUGCUAUGAGUAACGCUUGUAAGGAACUUGCCAUCUUUCUUACAACGGGCAUUGUCGUGUCAGCUUUUGGACUCCCUAUUGUAUUUGCCAGAGCACAUCUGAUUGAGUGGGGAGCUUGUGCACUUGUUCUCACAGGAAACACAGUCAUCUUUGCAACUAUACUAGGCUUUUUCUUGGUCUUUGGAAGCAAUGACGACUUCAGCUGGCAGCAGUGGUGAAAAGAAAUUACUGAACUAUUGUCAAAUGGACUUCCUGUCAUUUGUUGGCCAUUCACGCACACAGGAGAUGGGGCAGUUAAUGCUGAAUGGUAUAGCAAGCCUCUUGGGGGUAUUUUAGGUGCUCCCUUCUCACUUUUAUUGUAAGCAUACUAUUUUCACAGAGACUUGCUGAAGGAUUAAAAGGAUUUUCUCUUUUGGAAAAGCUUGACUGAUUUCACACUUAUCUAUAGUAUGCUUUUUGUGGUGUCCUGCUGAAUUUAAAUAUUUAUGUGUUUUUCCUGUUAGGUUGAUUUUUUUUGGAAUCAAUAUGCAAUGUUAAACACUUUUUUAAUGUAAUCAUUUGCAUUGGUUAGGAAUUCAGAAUUCCGCCGGCUCUAUUACUGGUCAAGUACAUCUUUUCUCUUAAAAUUAUUUAGCCUCCAUUAUUACAAAAAAUUAUAAAAAUAAGUUUUCAGUCAGUCAGGAUGACAUCACUCCCAAUGUUAUGCAGACAUACAGACGGUUGGCAUACGUUAUAGACUGUAUACUCAGUGCAAAUAUAGCUGCAUUUAUACCUCAGAGGGGCCAAGUGUUAAUGCCCAUGCCCUCCGUUAAGGGUUGUUGGUUUUACUGGUAGACAGAUGUUUUGUGGAUUGAAAAUUAUUUUAUGGAAUUGCUACAGAGGAGUGCUUUUCUUCUCAAUUGUUAGAAGAAUUUAUGUUAAACUUUAAGGUAAGGGUGUAAAAACAUUUUUGAGAUAAGGUUUUUAUUUAUGUUUAUUAUUGUUAGAGUGAGUUGCAAUGUGGGAAGAAAUGACAUUGAAAUUCCAGUUUUUGAAUCCUGUUUCUAUUUAUAAGUGAAAUUUGUGAUCUCCUAUCAACCUUUCAUGUUUUACCCUGUUAAAAUGGACAUACAUGGAACCACUACUGAUGAGGGACAGUUGUAUGUUUGCAUCAUAUAUGCCAGAAAACCUUCCUCUGCUUCCUCCUUUUGACUUAUUUGGUAUGUUGUAUAUAUUACAUAAAAUAACUUUUCAAAUAUAGUUUAAUAACACUUAGAAGUGUUUACUUACCUGGAAAAUAAUUGCUAUGCCGUACAUUCAGAGUGCCCCCUCCCCUGCAAGGCCUUGCCAUGAUUAACAAGUAACUUGUUAGUCUUACAGAUAAUUCAUGCAUUAACAGUUUAAGAUUUAGACCAUGGUAAUAGUAGUUCUUAUUCUCUAAGGUUAUAUCAUAUGUAAUUUAAAAGUAUUUUUAAGACAAGUUUCCUGUAUACCUCUGAACUGUUUUGAUUUUGAGUUCAUCAUGAUAGAUCUGCUGUUUCCUUAUAAAAGGCAUUUGUUGUGUGAGUUAAUGCAAAGUAGCCAAGUCCAGCUAUAUAGCAGCUUCAGAAACAUACCUGACCAAAAAAUUCCCAGUAACCAGGCAUGAUCAAUUUAUAGUGGUCGUUUACAUCUAAUAAUUAUCAGGACUUUUUUCAGGAGUGGGUUAUAAAAACAUUCAAGUUGGUCUGACAGUAUUUUGUUAAGGAUAUUUGUUUGUAUGUUUAUUCAGUAUACUUACAUAAAAAUUAUUUCGCCAUCAGCCAAAACUCAGUAAUCAUGACAGCUGUCUGUUGUUUUAUGAAGUUUAUUUCUCAAGAAAAUGGGAAUAAAUUUGGGAUUUGUUCAGCUUUUUUACUAAAGAUGCCUAAAGCCACAGGUUUUAUUGCCUAACUUAAGCCAUGACUUUUAGAUAUGAGAUGACGGGAAGCAGGACGAAAUAUCGGCGUGUGGCUGGAGCCUUCCCACUGGAGGCUGAAAGUGGCUUGUGGUAUUAUAAUGUUCAGAUUUCAAGAGGAAGGUGCAGGUACACAUGAGUUAGAGAGCUGGUGAGACAGUUGGGAACUCUUUGUGCUUGUGAUCUACUGGACUUUUUUUUGCAGGAAGUGCAUUCUCUGGUCCUUCCCUAUUUUCUGUUCUGGAUGUCAGUGCAGUGCACUGCUACUGUUUUAUCCACUUGGCCACAGACUUUUUCUAACAGCUGCGUAUUAUUUCUAUAUACUAACUGCAUUGGCAGCAUUGUGUCUUUGACCUUGUAUACUAGCUUGACAUAGUGCUGUCUCUGAUUUCUAGGCUAGUUACUUGAGAUAUGAAUUUUCCAUAGAAUAUGCACUGAUACAAUAUUACCAUUCUUCUAUGGAAAGAAAACUUUUGAUGAUGAAACAAUAAAGAUUUUAAAUAUCUAUUUUAGUUUGUGGGUGUUUUUGAAAUGAAAAUAUAUGGCACACUUUCAUUCUGAAGUGCAUUAACAUUCUAAUAAGGUGAUGUAAAGCAAGAUGACAUUGGUGUAAUGUUAGAGUUGCAGAAGUUUCCAUUCCAAAAUAAAAUGGAAACCAUAGUUACAGAUAUUACAAUGCAGCCCUGUAAUUUUGAGCUGUAGUAAAAGGAUUGGUAAUCUGGGAAGUAGAAUUUUUACAAAAUCUUUUACAAAAAUAGUCAUAAAAGGUUUUGUUGACAUUUAAGACUACUACUGAUCUAAAGGCAAGGUCCUACUUCUUAAAUUUUCAGAACAUUUUUAUGACUUCUUAUUAUGUAUUUAUUACCACUCAUUAUUAUAGCAUGUUACUUUUUGCAAACAUUUUAAACAAAAAAUAUUUCUGUUUGGUACACUGUGAAGAGAGAAAAGUACUGUUCUGUAUUUUC